AGAUGCAAGCACGUGGGCUUUGUUUCUCCUUUGUGCCAACAGCCAGGAUGCCACCGAAAUAAUAAGCACAAGAAAGCUCCAGGGCCUUAGAAGUUCUCAUGUCAUCAUUCAUGAUCGUGGUCUGUGUUUCCUCAUUCCCUGACUUAAACAGAGUCAGACACCAGGCCCCAGCCCUCCUUUUUAUCUUUUUAUCGCCACGCUUCUCAGAAAGUCAAAGUUCCUAAAUUCACUCAGGUAACAGAGCCCCUGGAAGUCAUGAGCUCCUUAAGGAAGGUCACAAUUAGCACUGCUAAUUCCAUCGUAGGAAAGUAGGGUCCAGACCCAAUCCUGGUGAGGUACAGGUUGCUUAGCCUUUAGGGCACAGGCUCUGGGGCAGGCAGAGCUCAGGUUGAAUCCCACCUCCAACACUUGCUAAGUGCAUGACCUCAGGAAAGCUAUUCAACUUCUCAGAGCCUCAGUGUUAUGACUGAAUUGUGUUCCCUUAAGAUUCAUAUGCUAAAAUCCUAACCCCCCAUGUGACUAUUUAGAGAUAGGGUCUUUAGGGAGGUCAUUAAGAAUAAAUGAGGUCAUGGGGGUGGGGCCCUAAUCUGAUAGUGUGGGUGUCUUCAUAAGAAGAAGAGUUACCAGAACCGCCUCUCUCUGCACAGACAAGAGGCCAUGUGAGGACACAGAGAAAGCAGCCGUUUACAAGCCAAGAAGAGAGGCCGCAUCACAAACCAACCUUUAUGGCACCUUGAUCUUAGACUUCUAGCUCCAGAACAGUGAGAAAAUGACAUUUCUGUUGCUUAAGCCACACAGUUCGUGGGUUUUGGUUAUGGCAGCCUGAGCUGACUAAUACACUCAGUUUCCUCAUUUGAAAAGCAGGGAUAAAACUAGUACUUGCGGCAUGACGUUAUUGUGAGAAUCCAAUGAGGAAACACACGUAAUGCCUUCCUGCUUCAUUUUCCUACGGCAUCUUCAACGCCUGGAACAGCCUCUGGCAGACAGUGGAUGUUCAAUAAAUACCCACUGAAUGGAUAAAUACAUCCAUCAAAAAAUGAAGCUGCCACACUAAAUAUGAGAACUUCUUUCUAAGCGCUUCCCUCGCCUUCAUCUCCUUAAUCGUUGGUCAUCACUCACCAGCAAAUGACAACAGUAGUAAAGGGUUUAAGAAAAGUGUCUGCAAGGCCAGCAUGCUGUUUUUAAUUGGAUCUGCCAAAUAAUGUAAUGUUGUCUAUGAGUUGAGAAAGGUGACACUGAUCAGAGAGCUGAAGGAAGCCUGAGAACCCUGGUCCAGCUUGGCUCUUCCUCUUAUCGUGCAGAGGGGCUGGAGACCACAGCUGGGGGAGGCCCGCCUAGGGGAGGCUCAGAGACCUGGGGCUGGGCCCUGAGAGUGUCCUGGAUGAAGUUGGUCCAGGGUUGGAGGCCACAGCAGAUCUACCUUCCUGGUGUUUAGGAGAUGCAAAUGAUGGGAACAAUGGAGCCCUUGUCCCCAGGCCAUUUGUGGCAGAUCCUGGGCUCCAGGGAGGCAAAGCUCCUCUGCCUCUGCCAUGGACAAGCUCAGUGGGAGCAGGCCCCGGUGAGUACUGGGACUCCUCUCUCCCCUGCCCUCCCCUCUUGUCUCUCUCUACCCCUCCUCUCCUGGGCACAGCCAUCCCAGGAGCUGUGCUGUCUCUGCCUGGCCCCUCUCUGCCCAGGGAGACCAUUCACGCGCCUCCACUUCCUGUCAGCACUAGGGCUCCCUGACUCCCGGCUUCCCCAGGGCACCAGCUCAUGCAGUUAUGCACCCACGGGCACCAGCUCUGCCCCCAGCCUCCUUCUCUGCUGCCCUGGUACCAGGGUACCUGUCAGUCACACUGUCAUGGAUGUGAAUGUCCCAGAACACAGCGUCUGUCUCAUAGAAACUCCAGGGCCCCUUGGGCAGAGUUGACUAGAAUGUGCUUGCAGGCUGGGGCCACCGCUCCCACCCCCCAGAUGUGUGGACUCCCCAGGUUGGAGAGAAGAUGCUCCCAGCCCUUCCUUCCUGCCUGCCCCAGGGACUUGGAGACACAAGAUCACUCUGGCCCCCUGGGUCCAUCAAAGCCAUCGCCACCCCUGCCUCAGCCCACCAUGCUGAAGGGAGCAGUGAGCCUGCCGGUGGCCGGAAAGCAGGGACCUAUCUUUGGGAGGCGAGAGCAGGGUGCAUCGUCCAGAGUGGUGCCAGGCCCUCCAAAGAAACCUGAUGAGGACCUCUACUUGGAAUGUGAGCCGGAUCCAGUCCUGGCUUUGACUCAGACUCUCAGCUUCCAAGUCCUGAUGCCCUCAGGCCCUCUGCCCAGGACAUCAGUGGUGCCCAGGCCUACCACAGCCCCCCAGGAAACUCGGAAUGGAACAGCAGAUGCUGCCUCUAAAGAAGGAAGGAAAUCGUCUCUUCCCUCUGUAGCCCCCACUGGGAGUGCCUCAGCUGCUGAGGACAGUGAUCUGCUGACUCAGCCUUGGUACUCGGGGAACUGUGACCGCUAUGCUGUUGAGAGUGCCCUGCUCCACUUACAAAAGGAUGGGGCCUAUACCGUGCGCCCCAGCUCAGGGCCUCAUGGCUCCCAGCCCUUCACCCUGGCAGUGCUUCUCCGAGGCCGGGUCUUCAACAUUCCCAUCCGGCGGCUGGAUGGCGGACGCCACUAUGCCCUGGGCCGGGAGGGCAGGAACCGUGAGGAGCUCUUCUCCUCCGUGGCGGCCAUGGUCCAGCACUUCAUGUGGCACCCUCUGCCCCUUGUGGACAGACACAGCGGCAGCCGGGAACUCACCUGCCUGCUCUUCCCCACCAAGCCUUGAGGCCACAGCGAAGUACACACCGCCUUUGGCCCCAGUUUGCUUCUUGUCCCGCCCCACCUUGGGCUGUCUUCCUCUCUCCUUCCCCACCCCUCCUCACCCUAGCCUUUCCCAGUGCCCACAAGCAGCAUUAAUGGGGAAAGCCUGCCUGGAGGCCCAGGGAAGGGUCCUGGAGACCCCACCCCAUGCUCACCUAGAGCCUUCCACUGCCCUCUCUGUUGCCUCUCCAAGGCUGACACCCUCUUCCUGGCCUCCAGGAAUGCAGGUGUCUGCCCAGUUCACUAGGUCCUGGAUGAAGGAACCGUGGUGGCCUAGACCAGUCAGGGGACAGCACAGGCACUGCUGGAACAGCAAAGGAUCCUCUCACAUCUACUUGUGGGCCUAGGGCACCCUGAGAGGGACUGGCCUACCUUGCACAAGUUCACAUUCAAUAAACAUUUGUUGAAUGAA